GAAUGAGAAAGCAGGUUGUGGCGGCGGCGCCCUGCUCUUCCCCGCUCGUCUGGGGCUUCUGCUGGCUAGUGGGGAGAAGUGCUCUUCUAGGGGGGCUUUUCUGGCCCUUGGCAGGGGUUUGGAGUUGGAGUCACAGGGGCCAAUAACUCAUCACCCCAGCACUUCGGAGGUGGCUCCUUGUGCCACGGACUCCGAGGAGUCCUUCAGCUACUGAACACUCAAAGCUGAGGAGGGCAAUUUGGUUUUGAUGCUGUGCCAGAAAUCUUCUGACAAUGAGUUACUGGAACUUGGAAAAAAGGAACUGUGUGCAGUACCGCAGGCAUUUUCUGGUGGACAACAGUGUGUUUCAUGUUGAAAGAUGCAUGAGUGUGAUGCAGUCCGGGACACAGAUGAUCAAGCUGAAACGUGGAACCAAAGGGCUUGUCCGCCUCUUUUACCUGGAUGAGCACCGGACACGCCUCCGAUGGCGACCCUCUAGGAAGAGUGAGAAGGCAAAAAUACUUAUUGAUUCCAUUUACAAAGUGACUGAGGGCCGGCAGUCUGAAAUAUUCCACAGACAAGCUGAGGGGAACUUCGACCCCAGCUGCUGCUUCACCAUCUACCAUGGCAACCACAUGGAGUCCCUGGACCUCAUCACCUCCAACCCCGAGGAGGCCCGCACCUGGAUCACAGGCCUCAAGUACCUGAUGGCUGGCAUCAGUGAUGAAGACUCCCUUGCCAAAAGGCAGAGGACCCAUGACCAAUGGGUGAAGCAGACCUUUGAGGAAGCUGAUAAGAAUGGUGACGGCUUGCUGAAUAUUGAAGAGAUACAUCAGCUGAUGCAUAAACUGAAUGUUAAUCUGCCCCGAAGAAAAGUCAGACAAAUGUUUCAGGAAGCCGACACAGAUGAGAAUCAGGGAACUUUGACAUUUGAAGAGUUCUGUGUUUUUUACAAAAUGAUGUCUUUGAGACGAGACCUUUAUUUGUUACUUUUGAGCUACAGUGACAAGAAAGAUCACCUAACUGUGGAAGAACUGGCUCAGUUUUUGAAGGUGGAGCAAAAGAUGAAUAAUGUGACAACGGACUAUUGUCUUGACAUCAUAAAGAAGUUUGAAGUUUCAGAAGAAAAUAAGGUGAAAAAUGUUCUUGGCAUAGAAGGCUUCACGAACUUCAUGCGUAGUCCUGCCUGUGACAUAUUUAACCCAUUGCACCAUGAAGUGUACCAAGACAUGGAUCAGCCCCUCUGCAACUACUACAUUGCUUCCUCUCACAAUACAUACCUGACUGGAGACCAGCUCCUUUCUCAGUCCAAAGUGGAUAUGUAUGCACGGGUGCUGCAAGAGGGCUGUCGCUGUGUGGAAGUUGACUGUUGGGAUGGCCCAGAUGGAGAGCCAGUAGUACAUCAUGGUUACACUCUCACUUCAAAAAUUCUCUUCAGAGAUGUUGUGGAGACCAUCAACAAGCAUGCCUUUGUGAAGAAUGAGUUUCCUGUUAUAUUGUCUAUCGAGAAUCACUGCAGUAUCCAGCAGCAAAGGAAGAUUGCUCAGUACCUGAAAGGAAUAUUCGGAGACAAACUGGACCUGUCAUCUGUUGAUACAGGGGAGUGCAAGCAGCUUCCAAGCCCUCAAAGUUUGAAAGGCAAAAUUCUAGUGAAGGGUAAGAAGUUGCCUUAUCACCUUGGGGAUGAUGCAGAGGAAGGGGAAGUUUCUGAUGAGGACAGUGCAGAUGAAAUUGAAGACGAGUGCAAAUUCAAGCUCCAUUAUAGUAAUGGGACCACUGAGCAUCAGGUGGAAUCUUUCAUAAGGAAAAAACUGGAGUCACUGUUAAAAGAAUCUCAAAUUCGAGAUAAAGAAGAUCCUGAUAGUUUCACAGUGCGGGCACUACUGAAGGCCACGCAUGAAGGCUUAAAUGCACACCUGAAGCAGAGUCCAGAUGUAAAGGAAAGUGGAAAGAAAUCACAUGGACGAUCCCUCAUGACCAACUUUGGAAAACAUAAGAAAACUACAAAAUCACGGUCUAAAUCUUACAGUACUGAUGAUGAGGAAGACACACAGCAGAGUACUGGCAAGGAGGGUGGCCAGCUGUACAGAUUGGGUCGCCGAAGGAAAACCAUGAAGCUCUGCCGAGAACUCUCUGAUUUGGUUGUGUACACAAACUCCGUGGCCGCUCAGGACAUUGUGGAUGACGGAACCACAGGAAAUGUGUUAUCAUUCAGUGAAACAAGAGCACAUCAGGUUGUUCAGCAAAAAUCAGAGCAGUUCAUGAUUUAUAAUCAAAAGCAACUCACGAGGAUUUACCCCUCUGCCUACCGCAUUGAUUCCAGUAACUUCAACCCUCUCCCCUACUGGAACGCAGGCUGCCAGCUAGUGGCACUGAAUUAUCAAUCUGAAGGACGAAUGAUGCAGUUAAACCGAGCCAAAUUCAAGGCAAAUGGCAAUUGUGGCUAUGUCCUCAAACCCCAGCAAAUGUGCAAAGGUACUUUCAACCCUUUCUCUGGUGACCCUCUUCCUGCCAACCCCAAAAAGCAGCUCAUCCUGAAAGUUAUCAGUGGACAGCAACUCCCCAAACCUCCAGACUCCAUGUUUGGAGAUCGAGGCGAGAUCAUUGACCCUUUUGUUGAAGUUGAAAUUAUUGGAUUGCCAGUAGAUUGUUGUAAAGAUCAAACCCGUGUGGUAGAUGACAAUGGAUUUAACCCUGUGUGGGAAGAAACACUGACAUUUACAGUACACAUGCCAGAAAUAGCUUUGGUUCGGUUCCUUGUGUGGGAUCACGAUCCCAUUGGACGAGACUUUGUUGGACAAAGAACUGUGACCUUCAGCAGCUUAGUGCCUGGCUACCGGCAUGUCUAUUUGGAAGGACUGACAGAAGCAUCCAUAUUUGUACACAUAACCAUCAAUGAAAUCUAUGGAAAGUGGAGCCCUUUAAUACUCAACCCCAGUUAUACUAUAUUGCACUUUCUAGGAGCUACAAAGAACAGACAACUCCAGGGUCUGAAGGGACUGUUCAAUAAGAAUCCUAGGCACAGUUCUUCAGAAAACAAUUCCCAUUAUGUACGGAAGCGAUCCAUUGGAGAUAGAAUUCUGCGACGCACAGCUAGCGCCCCAGCCAAAGGCAGGAAAAAGAGCAAAAUGGGCUUCCAAGAAAUGGUGGAGAUAAAGGAUUCUGUGUCCGAGGCCACAAGAGAUCAAGAUGGCGUGCUGAGGAGGACCACACGCAGUUUGCAAGCACGCCCUGUCUCUAUGCCUGUUGACAGAAACCUUCUGGGAGCUUUGUCGCUGCCUGUAUCUGAAACAGCAAAAGACAUUGAAGGAAAAGAAAACUCUCUAGGGUCACUCCGGAGAGGAACUGUAUGGAGGUAGUGGUCCCUUUCUGGAGAACCUCAACAUAUCAUACCACACUCUCUUUGAAUUGACUCAAGGUCUUCCCUUCUCCAUCAGUUGGUUAUAGAGGAUUUCCCAUGAGGCCAUAAGUAUGAGUUGAGGGAGUGACACCAGAGCCAAACAGGUAGGUGAUCUGAAGGUCUGGGCAAACAAAUCACAUUUUUUGUGUGUGUCUUCUGGACUACUUGAGUCUUUUCUUAAAAGUACCAUUUUCUUCAUAUAAUAGUUUGCUCCUGUGCUUCUCAACCUUUUUCUGGGCGUUUCUAUUAAGACCAUGCUCAUGAUGGGUAGCUCCAACUGCAGUUACAUGGUGGACCAUAGUCAUGCUCUCAGGUUUUACCUCACAGGAUAUGUCCCUGCAUGCUCUAGAUCUCUGGGUCCCUAAAAAUCUCACUGGUGUUGCAGGCCCCUUAAUCAUUAGGUACUUAUGGUCUAACUUGUGAUAUGUCUGUAUCUUAUCAGGACAUUCAAGUUGAUUGAUCUAUUCUCUUUAUUAGGUCCAAUUAGAAAAAUGUCAAUCAAUAUAGAAGACUAGCAUAAUGUGCUGUGACAUAUGAAGAUGAUAGAGAUCAUUACAAAACAUACCAUUAUAGACAGUAGAAUUAACACAGACCCAGGGCAAGGCCGUGAAGAUUUACUGCUGUCCUUACAAAUGUAAAGGUGAGCUGCUUUUGAUUUUCCCUACUGAUGAAAGUCAGGAAUAAAGCAUACAGCAAAAUAAUAGACACAAACUAAGUGCCAGAGGUUAGACUGGUAUACUCUUAAAAAGAAAAAUUAUAUCUAGCACAGAAGCUGCAAUUGUGGAUACCACCUGGUUGAAUUUGCAGUAGCCCACUAGCACCCACCACUAUCUAUCUAUCUAUCUAUCUAUCUAUCUAUCUAUCUAUCUAUCUAUCUAUCUAUCUUCUAUAUCUAUCUAUCUAUCUAUCAUCUAUCAUCUAUCUUUGUGUAUUUGUGUGUAUGUUUGCAGAGACCAGAUAGAUGAAAUGACUAGGGAUACAAUGGGAAUUGCCAUCCAUGAAUCCUUUAAGUCUUUGUUGGUACUAAUUUCUGCAGUUCAUCUUGGGAGGAGAUAUUGCUUCUGAUUAACUAUCUUGGCCUGGAGGGGGGGCUAACACUGCUCCUUUCUAUCAUAAAGUCCCUUAACUCAGGUCAGGAAACUAAGGGCCAACUUCUAAGUAUAUCUAUCCCAUUAGACAUUCAGAGACUAGAGAAGUAACAGAAUGGGUCCUUAUAUCUAUUGGACCCAUUGUAAGAUGGACUUGAGCCCAAAUCCCAUUUAUAAUCUGAUACUGAUAAUACUCCAUUUCCAACUACAAGACAAUGGUGGUGGUGUUUUGUGUCCCCUGGUAUUGGUGCCAACUGUGAGAAUACCUAGACUUUUUGUCUGUCCAGUACAUAUUUUGGCAAAUUUGGGCAAGGAUUAAAGAAAUAAAUGUCAUGCUUGUGUGACAUUGUGAGGAACAAGCUUUCCUUUCAAUCACUGGGUUCUAGAUCUGUGAGCUGACUUAGAUCUAGUAACUAGAAAUUGCAACUGUCCAUUAUACUGUCCAGCAUCAUCCUAUGUUCAUCAGUUCUCUAUUAUUUCUGAUUGUACAAAUCAAAACGCUGGUUCAAUGAUUCUUAAACUUUAGUGUGCAUCUCAACCACCUAGAGAGCUAGUUAAAACACAGAUUGCUGGGCCACAUCCCCAGAAUUUCUGCAUCAGUAGCUGAGAUGAGGCUCAAGAAUUUUCAUUUCAAACAAGUUCCCAGAUGGUGCUAAUGCUGCUGAUCUCAGGUCCACACUUUGAUAACCACUGCUGUAGAUGGCUGCUUGUCUGUGUCAUCUUUGGGAAAAUCAUCAUUUCUUAGCUAUAAUAAAACAUCACUUUGGGACAAGGCACCUUCACUGCCCCUCUGGCCAUGCUGCUCAUUAUGGUCAUUACAUCCACCUGGGCUCUGCCUUGAUCAACUCCCCAUAUCCCCAUUGCUAUUAGAGUCAACCCUGGCCUGACAGGACAACCAACUGUGGGUUCUCAGUGAUGCUGGUACUCAGGCCCUCCUGGAAAAUAUAAACAGCUGGGGGAUUCAGUGUCUUUAUUCUAAUAGUCCCCCUUUCUUGAGCCUCUGACCCCUUUCUCAAUUACUCUGCCAAAGAGGUUCCAACAUUUUAACUCAAUUUACUUUACAUUUUCACUCAAUUUAAUUUACAUUGUGAAUCCAGGCUUCGAGGAGUCAUCUCAGCAAACUGCUAGGACUGGUGUCCUUGUUAGACAUGAAAUUCGAAAUUAUGGUUGAGUUAUACACUCUAAUAAAUAUUUUCCUCUUCAGCCUUAAUUCUACUUCCCUGGUCUAACACCCUCAAGAUUUACCCAUACAGGUGUUUCUCUGGUUCUUGUUUGAUACAUUUAUGAUCUGGUCCCACCACCUGCCAUAGAUCAAACAUGGUCACAGAAUGCCUUAAAAUAGCAAUUAGCUGCCUCAUACUACCUAUCAAGGAUUUCAAUGUCAUCAUAAGUAUCUAACCACUGCCAAAGUCCUAUAAUUAUCAUCAUCCUUAUAUUGGUAAAUUGCAGCGACAACUUAAUAUUCAAAGACUUACCUUAAACCCCCACCUUAUCCCAAUUAGCCACAAAUAAGAGCUUUAGUAAUUCUAAUGUCACAGCUUGCCCGUUGUUAUUACUAACUAUCCCACUCUGGAACCAGUUUUCUCAGCGUUGGUUUCUUGGAGUAGACAGCAGAAGGGGAUAGCUUUUGUGCUACUGUUUUAUGGAGGUACAACCCUAGGGAAGCAAGAGUAAGGGGGAAAAGAGUGCAGUAAAGAAAGAGGGUAGGAAAAUACAAGGUAGAGUAUUAUAAUACCAAGGUAACCAUGCCUUCAGAACAAAAUAGCUGGUUGUCCCGUCUUUUAAGACAUUUCCAGAGAGGUCAAAUAAAACCAUCGCAUCUCAGAGCAGUCCGUUAGGGGAAGAAAUAAUAGACAAUGUAUCUGCUGACUUUUUUCUAUCUCUUGUCUUGCAUUGUUGAAAUCUGCCUCCAUGGGACUUAACUAUUUGAAGUCCACAUUUCCAGUUUACCCACACUUUUUUUCUUUCUUUCUCUUUCUAAACAUGGUUUCUUUCUUUCUUCCUUUCUUUCUUUCUUUCUUUCUUUUUCUCUUUCUUUCUUUUUCUUUUUCUUUCUUUCUCUUUCUUAUUUCUCUCUCUUCUUUCUCUUUCUUUCUUUCUUUCUUUCUUUCUUUCUUUCUUUCUUUCUUUCCUUCCUUCCUUCCUUCCUUCCUUCCUUCCUUCCUUCCUUCCUUCCUUCCUUCCUUCCUUCCUUCCUUCUUUCUUUCUUUCUUUCUUCUUUCUUUCUUUUUUUUUUUUUUUUUGACAUGGAGUCUUGCUCUGUUCCCCAGGCUGGAGUGCAGUGGUGCAAUCUUGGCUCACGGCAACCUCCGCCUCCCAGGUUCAAGUGAUUCUCCUGCCUCAGCCUCCUUAGUAGCUGGAAUUACAGGCAUGCACUACUACGCCCCACUAAUUUUUGUAUUUUUGGUAGAGAUGGGGUUUCACCAUGUUGGCCAGGGUGGUCUUGAACUCCUGACCUCAAGUGAUCUGCCUGCCUUGGCCUCCCAGAGUGCCGGGACUACAGGCAUGAGACACUGUCCCCGGCCUUACCCACACUUUCUAAUCUAUCCCUGAGGAAGCUGGAGCCUCUCUGGGUCCCCUCUGGCAGAUUAUGAAGAUCUCCCUUUGUCAUUUGGAGCUGUGCACGGGAACUCCUCAGUUGGUGGUGGCAGUGCCACAGAAGUUUGGAUGUAAUAGCCAUGGGUGAGGUGUGAUCUAUUGCUGAGGCUGCUCUGGCGGGGAAGCAAGGGUGACAUUGAUGGGGGUGAUGGUAUUGGUGGGGCCAAGCAGAUCUGGCUUGGCACAUAAAAUGCAUCCAGCUCAGUCAGCAUAUUUAACACUUAUCAAAGACAUAUGAAGAAGCAAUUUUAAUAUAGUAUUAAGAUUUAGAAAUUGGAGAAAAAAGAUUUAACCGAAUUCCUUGACCUUAUGAAGUUAUAAAAUAUUUUGUGAAACAUACACAUAAAUAGAUAAUAUUAAUAUAAUGUACUAAGUGCAGCGACAAAGGCAAGCAUGGGUUAAAUAGGAAGAACAGAAAGGGGCAGCUAGCUUGGUUUGAGGGGCCUGGUCAGGGAAAAUUUUCUGGAGGCAGGACCAACUACAGAGGCAUGCAAUCAGGUAGCUUAGGGCCUUACCCUCAGAAUUGUUAGUGCUUGGGGCUUAAUGCUCUGUGGCCCCCUUUUGAAAUUUUUAGUUUCAUCUUUGAAUUUGUGUUUUGUAAAUGAAGUCCAAUGGGACAAUGGAGCACAUGAUGGGCACUUGAAGCCUCUGCUCAUCUUGUGCUAUUCACUUUUGGCUGCCUCCCUCCUCCCUGGCCCAUUUACAGCCUGCUAGAACUCUAGGGCAGGAGGAGGCCAUCAUCCUCCUUUUUCCCAGCAGAGGCCACAGCAUAGAAGCAUGGAGGUUCAAGGUCAGGUUUGGCCAUCACUCUUUUUCCCCAGCAGGGGCCACAGUGUAGAAGCAUGGAGGGUCAAGCUCAGGUUUGUGCGCCACAGUGUCCGGGGCAACGCAAGGCAGCAGUUGUUUCUGCCUUGGCUGGCAGAGCAACAGCCGUGUUUGGAUCAGCAGGGACUUCUCGCCUGUUCCCAAAUCAGAUGCCAAGUGUUUCCCUGUGCAAAGUCUAAAUAUUUUGGAUUGGGAUGACCUCCUGUGGAAGGGAUAUGUUGAAUUCCACCUGUGAGAUUUUCGUUUUUUAUUUUGCACUGGGCCACCCAAAUUAUGUGGCCACCUUGCCUGGAGGCAGCGAUGAUGCUCAAAUUGAUUUGUGAAGGAUGAGUAGAAAUUUUCCAGGUGAAAAAGGUGGGAAAGGGGUUGAAAGGGUCUACUAAGGAGUGGGAAGGAAACAAAAGAUUUCACCAUUUAUGCAGAAAAUGUAUUUUUUUCUCUCUUGAAUAUCUUGGCGGAUGGUAGUUCCAUUUCCUGAAAUGGAGAAGAGAAGGUAUGAGUGGUUCAGGGAGGAAUCUGAGUUUCCUCUGGGUAUGUUAAUUUGAGAUUCCCAUUAGACCUCCUUUUGGAGAUGUCUAGUUGACAGUCUGGAGUCAGGGGCAGAAAUAAGGGCUGGAAAUAGGCUUAACGCCAUGGGAUCAAGUGAGGUUGCCCAGGUAGGGAAUGUAAAUAGAGCAGAAAAGAGGAUUUGGGCACCUUUGUUUUAGAUCAAACUUGUCCAACCCAUGGCCUGUGGGCUAAAGGCAGCCCAGGAUGGCUUUGAAUGUGGCCCAACACAAAUUUGUAAACUUUCUUAAACCAUUAUGAGAUUUUUUUUUUUUUUUUUAGCUCAUUAGCUAUCAUUAGUGUUAGUGUAUUUUAUGUGUGGCCCAAGACAGUUACCUUUCUUGCAGUGUGGCCCAGGGAAGCCAAAAGAUUGGACACCCCUAUUUAAAUGAUGAUCAGAAGAGGAGGAUACGGUAAAGAAGGAGGACAUUCAGGGGAGUAUCAUAGAGAAAGAGACGAAAGUAUUUUGAGAAGGAGGUCAGCACAUAGUUUGAAAAGUUUUAAGUCAACAUCAGAAUUUCAAGGUAUUUCAUAUAAAAUGUGGACUUUUAGCCUGUCUUGAACAAUCGACAGGGCAGACAACACUGGCCCACAUUCUGCGUGGUAAGAACCCAGUUGCAGGCACACAGAGCCUGUGCUCAUGAAUGGGCGUGCAUGUUCCAGCUUCACUUCUCCACCUAGUAGUCCUUGUCACCCUCAUUAUUAGGGCUUAUCAGUCCUCAUUUGUGAUUGUGCUUUCAUCACUGAAAGUCCUGCAGGCAAGAACUAUUUCUCUGUGUGUAACUCUCCAACAAAGCCAGGAAAAGAAAAGAUAGCCUAUGGGUUUAAAAACAAAAUUGGAGAAAGUGUAUUUCUUUGUAGAAGUAAAGAAUAUUCUGUGUGCUUAAUUAGGAAACAAAGCCUCUUCAAAAGAAACAGCUUUGCCUGUUUUACUCAGUUAUAAUCCAUUACCUCCCUGGCUUCUGUAUGCUUUCCAGUUGACCCUACCCUAAAUUCAUUUGCAAAUUCUGUUCCCAGAACCAAUAUUUCUCAAAUGCUUUCAUGUUAUUUUUCUUGCUCAAUUAACUUCAGUGAGUAGUGAAUGUUGGUGUCCACAUUUUCUGAACGCAGAAUAUACUAAUUGAAGCUGUUUUUAAAAUUUAAAUGCACACUUAGGAGCAUUUAUCUACCAUUCUCUGCUGACCCUCCUCCCAGGUGCUAAUUUAGGACCAAUGCCAGUUCAGAUCAAAUUCUACCUGAAAGACUAUUUUCUAAUCAUGCCACAUGUAGGGACCAUCUUGGGGACAAGACAGCAUCUGUGUGGCAGGAGUAGUUCACUCCAGUCCCCUUGAGAGCCCUUGCCUCUGGGGGAGCUGCAACCAGUGGCAGGGUGAGGGUUGUGGCUUCUGCAUCCCAGGGUCGGCUCCUUCUCACCACCCCCUUCCCUUCCUCCAAUUCCUCCCUGAGAGCCUCACCUUCCCUAGUUCAUCACAUUCCGGUGACACAAAUAUCCUAUUUAUGGGUAUUAAUUAUAUUAACACAUAAUAGUAUUGUAAAUUAGAAACUUCAUCUCUCAGGAGAAAAGAAAACUAGUUGGUUUUAUCCUUUCUUGCAAAUUCAAGGUGGUACUAUAGACUAGUGGUUAGAAGCUUCACCUCUUUGCCAAAGUGCUUGCAUUCAAAUCCCUUUUCCUUUAUAUCUUAUUAUGACCUGUAAAAUGGGAAUAAUGACCCACCUCAUCUUUUAUGUGUAACAGGGGGACCAGCCCAAACUGGGCCUACUCUGUUGAUAACAAAAUGUCGAGUUACCUUGUAGGUAUAGCAGAGGAAAACUACAAGUCAUGUAGUCCAGGAAGACAUAAUUAAAAAAAGCUUUGACUUCUAACAACAUCUUGAACCAAUGAUUCCUUCCCUGGAAACCAAAAAGACUGAGACAUGACUGGAACCUGAACACUAGGACUCUUUCAAAAGCAAAGGGUCUCUUGGCCCUGAAGAGCUGGGGCUAAAAUCUGCCUCAAUACACCUUACCAUAAAUGGUCAAAUUUGAAACUGUCCAAUCAGACCCAUGCCAAGUCAACAUUCCUAAAUCCUUUUCUUUGCCCUCUGAUCCCUUGUAACUUUCUUUUUUCUUUUUUUCUUAUUUAUUUAUUUAUUUAAGAUGGGGUCUUGUUCUGUCACUCAGGUUGGAGUGGAGUGGCACAAUCAUGGCUCACUGCAGCCUAGACCUCCUGGGAUCUAAUGAUCCUCCUGCCUCAGUCCCCCAAGUAGCACCACUACGUCCAGCUAAUUUUUGUAUUUUUUUGUUGAGAUGCUGUUUUGUCAUGUUGCUCAGGCUGAAAAACUUUCAUUAGAUUCCAAAUCAGGGAGACAGAUUUGAGCCCAACUCCUUGCUGGCUGAUUUGCAGUAAAACCUUUCUUUUCUCAAAAGCUGGUGCCAUGGUAUUGGCUUCUGUGUACAUCAGAUAGCAAGCCCAUUUGCUCAAUAACAUGAAGAUUAUAUGAAUUAAUACAUAAAGUUCUUAAUUAGUAGAAGUUGGCACAUAGUAAAUGCUCAAAUUUUUGCUGCUAUACUAUAUCACUAUUAUGGUUAUCUUAUGGCAUACUAUUAUAUCUUCUUUCCAUUUAAUUAUUGUAUAACCACUAGGCUGACUUAUUCUUUUCUCUGGAGUACAAUUUUAAUUUUUUUCCCACAGACCUUUCUGACUUAUGCAUAAUUCCCUCCCUGUAUCCAUCCUUUUCUACUUAUAAAGAUAGAGAGAAAUUUCUAUUUUUAAUUUGCAGAAAGAUGCAUAUUUAUUAGAAGAAAUAGAAUAUCUAUAUUUAUCUAUAGAUAAAUACAUAUUUAUAAUUUAUUAUCAGAAAUUAAUCAUAAAUUAUUAAUUUCUAAUUAUUAAUCAGAAAUUAUUAAUUUCUAAUUAUUAAUCAGAAAUUUAUAUAGAAACAAAAUAACUCAUGUCAAAAUCCUUCACUUGGUUCCAGUUACAUUUUUCUUAAUACUCCCAUUCUCUUCAUUAAUCAGUUCUUUAUUCUGAAUUCCAGACAUUUAUGCAUUGAAUAAGUAGUCAUUUUGCGUUGUAUUUUAAUGCAAGUUUAUAUGAUUUACUUUAAGUAAUGUUUUGAAUUUAUUUUUUCAUUUUUGAACUUUUCAUUUUGAAAUGAAGACUUGGUAAACAGUUUCAAAAAUAGUACAAAUAAUUCCUGCAUAUCCUUCACCCAGUUCCCCCAAAUGUUUCAUCUCAAAAAACCACAGUAAAAUGAUCAGAAUCAGGAAGUUAGCACUAUACAAUAAUAUUAACUUAUUUAUGGUCUCUAUUUAAAUUAUACCAUGUAUCCCACUAAUAUCCUUUUUCUGGCCUAGAUUCCAAUCCAGGAUCCCACAUUGCAUUUAAUUGACAUAUCUUCUUGAUUUCCUUCCAUCUGUGAAAGUUCCUUAGCCUUUGUCUUUCAUGGUCUUGACACUUCUGAAGAGUGUUAAGAUUUAAUUCAGAUUAUGCCUUGUUGGCAAAAUUCCAUACACCUGAUGUAAUGCUGCUUCCACUGGGUGUGAGGAGGGCUCUUCUAUUGGAAAAUAAGCUUCAUCAGAAUUUAGGGGCUCACUAUCACCAGCAUUAUCAGAGUCUUCCCACAUGUACCCACUUUAACUUACAGGAUCCAACUUAUUUCCUGAUCGAUAUCCUCAUUUUAAUAGUAGAUACCUUGUGAGGCUGGGAGUUCAACUUGCAAUAUAUUUCAGUUAGUCACAGAAUGGGAUACUCUGCAUUUAAUUUUCAGCAAUCUCAGCCUUGUAUUAUAGGAGAUAAGGGUCUCCUUCAUAGCAUACAUAGAUGUUUUGAGGUCAUUUAUGUGGCACUUGAGGUGGGAAUUUGAAUCCCAGAGCUCAUCCUUAUUUCAUCAUUUUGCCCAUUGACAUCAGGAACAACCAUCUAAUGUCAUUACAUUUAUUAGACUCCCCAAAAUGUUCAAAAGUAUUAUAUACAUAGUCACCCAGCUCCUUCCUUCUUGUACUUCCUUCAGAUCAAGCCAUACUUGAUCUGGCCAUAAAGGUACCCUAAAUAUCUCCACUUGAUAACCCUAACUAACAGUGCUCUUUUUACUACUGAAGAUAGAGUCAUUAGUGUCUUUAAAUCCAAUCAGAUUAGACUCUCAAUUCUAGAAGCCCCAGAACCAAUUACUCCUGAUAACAAAAUCAUCUAUGUUAACCAGGGUUCUCCAAAGAAACAGGGUGAUAUGGUUUGGCUCUGUGUCCCCACCCAAAUCUCACCUUGAAUUAUACUCCCAUAAUUCCCAUGUGUUGUGGGAGGGACCCAGUGGGAGAUAAUUUGAAGCAUGGGGCAAUUCCCCCAUACUGUUCUCAUGGUAGUGAAUAAGUCUUACGAGAUUGAUGGUUUUAUCAAGGAUUUUUGCUUUUGCAUCUUCCUCAUUUUCUCUUGCUGCCACCGUGUAAGAAGUGCCUUUCUCCUCCUAUCAUGAUUCUGAGGCCUCCCCAGUCAUGUGGAACUUGUAAGUCCGAUUAAACCUCUUUUUCUUCCCAGUCUUGGGUAUGUCUUUAUCAGCAACAUGAAAACAGACUAAUACAUAGGGCCAGUAGGAGAUAGAGAGAGAGAAUGUAUGUGUGUGUGAGAGAGAGACAGAGAGAGAGGGAUUGAGAGAGAUUUAUUAUAAGGAAUGGGCUGAUGUGAUUAUGGGGACUGAGAAGUCCCGGCAGAAGAGCUGAUGGUACAUACAUUCCAGUUUGAGUAGGAAGGCCUGAGAAGCAAGUGAGCUGAUAGUGUUGGUUCCAGUCUGACAGUGAAGGUCUGAGAACCAGGAAAGCCAAUGAUGUAAGAUUCAGUCUGAAUUUAGGCCCAAAAGCAGAAGACUUCUGUCACAGUUUGAAGACAGGAAGAGAGAAAACAUUCUUUCUCACUUAUAUUAGGUUGGUGCAAAAGUAUUUUGCCAUUACUUUUAAUGGCAAAAACCAUGAUUACUUUGCACCAACAGAAUACUUUUAGUCCAUUCAGGCCUCCAAAAAAUGGAAAGAGGCCCGCACACAUUGCAGAUGGAAAUCUGCUUUAUUCAGUUUACUAAUUCAAAUGUUAACCUCAUCAAGAAAUACCCACAUAGACAUUCCCAUAAGUAAUGUUUAGCUAAAUAUCUGGGCACUACAUGGCCCUGUUAAGUUGACACAUAAAAUGAACCAUCACACCUUCUAAACACAUCAAAUCAGGAGGCACAUAAUGACAUUUUGUCUAAUUACUAGUGAUGUUAACUUAGAUCACUUGGAUAAGGCAGUCUUUCAAAUUUUCUUCACUUAACAUUAUUUUCCUCUUUGUAUUUGGUAAAUUUCUCGUGGCAAGAUAAUUGAGACCAUGUAAAUAUCCUGUUUUUCAUCACACCCUUACCUAUUAAUGAUUCUUGAUUGAGGUAAUUAUUACUGUAAUGUUAUCAAAUGAUGAUUUUAUAUUUCUGUUAUUUCUUCUAUAUUUAUUAAUUUGAAUUCUCUUAUUUAUUUCUUGAAUGAUUGGUAUCAGUAUGGACUCAUCAAUAUAUAUUUUUUAUUUUGGGGGUUAUAGUCCAUUAUUCUCAUUAUUAAUUUUGUUACUCAACUUGUCAUAGAUUUGGGCAUUAGGGGAUCUUCUUUAAAUCAUAUUUAAACAGCUUUGCUGUAUGAAUCCUCAUGGUUAGGUAUGUAAGGUUUGUAUAAAUAAACAAAUUUUCUCUAUUA